CCUUUCACUUUCGGUCUCUGGCUGUCACCCGGCUUGGCCCCUUCCACACCCAACUGGGGCAAGCCUGACCCGGCGACAGGAGGCAUGAGGGGCCCCCGGCCGAAAUGACAGUGCUGGCGCCAGCCUGGAGCCCAACAACCUAUCUCCUCCUGCUGCUGCUGCUGAGCUCGGGACUCAGUGGGACCCAGGACUGCUCCUUCCAACACAGCCCCAUCUCCUCCGACUUCGCUGUCAAAAUCCGUGAGCUGUCUGACUACCUGCUUCAAGAUUACCCAGUCACCGUGGCCUCCAACCUGCAGGACGAGGAGCUCUGCGGGGGCCUCUGGCGGCUGGUCCUGGCACAGCGCUGGAUGGAGCGGCUCAAGACUGUCGCUGGGUCCAAGAUGCAAGGCUUGCUGGAGCGCGUGAACACGGAGAUACACUUUGUCACCAAAUGUGCCUUUCAGCCCCCCCCCAGCUGUCUUCGCUUCGUCCAGACCAACAUCUCCCGCCUCCUGCAGGAGACCUCCGAGCAGCUGGUGGCGCUGAAGCCCUGGAUCACUCGCCAGAACUUCUCCCGGUGCCUGGAGCUGCAGUGUCAGCCCGACUCCUCAACCCUGCCACCCCCAUGGAGUCCCCGGCCCCUGGAGGCCACAGCCCCGACAGCCCCGCAGCCCCCUCUGCUCCUCCUACUGCUGCUGCCCGUGGGCCUCCUGCUGCUGGCCGCUGCCUGGUGCCUGCACUGGCAGAGGACGCGGCGGAGGACACCCCGCCCUGGGGAGCAGGUGCCCCCCGUCCCCAGUCCCCAGGACCUGCUGCUUGUGGAGCACUGACCUGGCCAAGGCCUCAUCCUGCGGAGCCUUAAACAACGCAGUGAGACAGACAUCUAUCAUCCCAUUUUACAGGGGAGGAUACUGAGGCACACAGAGGGGAGUCACCAGCCAGAGGAUGCAUAGCCUGGACACAGAGGAAGUUGGCUAGAGGCCGGUCCCUUCCUUGGGCCCCUCUCAUUCCCUCCCCAGAAUGGAGGCAACGCCAGAAUCCAGCACCGGCCCCAUUUACCCAACUCUGUACAAAGCCCUUGUCCCCAUGAAAUUGUAUAUAAAUCAUCCUUUUCUACCA